CACAAUUGACAGCCUCAAGGUUCCUGGCUUUUUGAACCACCACAGACAUCUCCUUUCCCGGCUACCCCACCCUGAGCGCCAGACACCAUGAACCUUCCUUCCACAAAGGUCUCCUGGGCCGCCGUGACGCUACUGCUGCUGCUGCUGCUGCUGCCGCCCGCGCUGUUGUCGUCCGGGGCGGCUGCACAGCCCCUGCCCGACUGCUGUCGUCAAAAGACUUGCUCUUGCCGCCUCUACGAGCUGCUGCACGGCGCGGGCAAUCACGCGGCCGGCAUCCUCACGCUGGGCAAGCGGAGGUCCGGGCCCCCGGGCCUCCAGGGUCGGCUGCAGCGCCUCCUGCAGGCCAGCGGCAACCACGCCGCGGGCAUCCUGACCAUGGGCCGCCGCGCAGGCGCAGAGCCAGCGCCGCGCCCCUGCCUCGGGCGCCGCUGUUCCGCCCCGGCCGCCGCCUCCGUCGCGCCCGGAGGACAGUCCGGGAUCUGAGUCGUUCUUCGGGCCCUGUCCUGGCCCAGGCCUCUGCCCUCUGCCCACCCAGCGUCAGCCCCCAGAAAAAAGGCAAUAAAGACGAGUCUCCAUU